AUCCCCCGGGAGCCCUGGCUUCCUGGGUGGGGGGCGCAGGGCAGGGCGGGGCGGUUCCUCCUGAGAGGCACCUGUGCACGGGCUGCAGGGACCCAUGCGGUGCAGAUGAGCCUCCUGGACACCGCGUCACAUGGCAGGGAGCUGUCGCUGCCAGAUCAAUGAUUAGGCAUGAAUCAGGCUGUGGCCUCGCUGCGCUCCUGCAGGGCUUUCUUUUGAAACUGGGAGCAGGGAAAGGCUCCUCUUGUAAAGGCCCAACUUUUUCCAUCCGUGGAGCCCAGAUUUUUGCCUGGUGACAUGAAUUAGCAGAGAGGACCGUGUUCCUUCCACAAUUAUUUCGCAGACGUUAUCUCUUCAUUAGAUGUGCCAGAAGCCAUUUAUCCACAAGUCACGUGAUUUAACAUAUGGCUCCCGUGUGGUUCCUGCCCGCUCCGUGUGGGCUACCGCUGGGAGUGCACGGGCAGGAUGGAGGGACACUCGGGGGGUGAGAAUCGCCACCUGGGAGCUGCCAUCCCCUCCACCAUCGGCCUCAGCUUCCUCUGGCGGGCAGGGUUGGGCUUGGUCCUGGUCAGCAGGGCCGCACCCCUGCCAGACCUGCACCACCUUGCCUGGCCUUUCCUCCCUGAAGAGGGGCACGAGCGGCAGUGGGUUGCCCCAUUUCCCAGGUUCCUUGACUCGGGACAAGGGAGGCUGAGAAUAUCUGCAGUGGCCUCGGGCUCUCCUCCCUGAGGCCCAUGGCUAACCUGGUUUGCAAAUCUACACCACCGCCUCCCCUUCAUGGAAAAAACCAGGCCCGAUGGGACCCCCGGCGUGGGAACUGGCAGCUGUAGGAUGCAUGGGUGUCAACCCUGCCUGCCACGUUCAGCUGUAACCAGAGCCGCCCACGGAGCCGGGCGCUGGGCCUCUGCGGGCACAGCCACUUAGCAGCCAACCUUGCUGCCUUGGGCUGGCCCCCUUGUCCUUGUGGGGAAUCUGAAGGUAGAGCAGGCUCCCCGACCCCCAGUCCUGAGGCUUGUCCUGGAAGGACCCCUGCCCCCUCCCUCAUCUCCCCUGUGCCUGAGUCUGUCCGGCUGUUCUCCUCUCCCCCAGCCCCAGUCCUGAGGCUUGUCCUGGAAGGACCCCCGCCCCCUCCCUCAUCUCCCCUGAGCCUGAGUCUCCAGCCGGUUCUCUGCCCUUGUAUUCCGAGUCCCAGGGCUCCUGUUUCCAGCCCUGCCUCGGACCGCAGGGUGCUGACCUGCCUUCCCCAGGUGCCAGUUUCUCAUCAGGGCGUGGUGCCCGCCCUUAUCCCCUGCAUGUGACAGUGGAGGCCCAGUCCCCAAGUGUGGGUGCUGACUCACAGGGAAGAGCUGCUGGGAGCCCUAUGACAGGUGUCCGCCCACCUCAGGGAACCUGUGGGUCCCAGCACAACCGGCGCUGUUGAGCGCAGGCGGCGGGCAGCCAGGCACCUGUUCAGAGCAAUCCCACGGGAAUGGCGGCCCCGCUCACACAGGCGCCGGGAUGCAGGGCUGAGGUCCGGCCUCUUUGGCCUACCCCCGUUGGCUCCGCUGCCCCAGGUCGAUGAGUCCCCUGUCAACGACAGCCAUGGCCGGGCUCCCGAGGAGGGGGAUGCAGAGGUGAUGCAGCUGGGGUCCAGCUCCCCCCCUCCUGCCCGCGGGGUUCAGCCCCCCGAGACCACCCGCCCCGAGCCACCCCCGCCCCUCGUGCCGCCGCUGCCCGCCGGAAGCCUGCCCCCGUACCCUCCCUACUUCGAAGGCGCCCCCUUCCCUCACCCGCUGUGGCUCCGGGACACGUACAAGCUGUGGGUGCCCCAGCCGCCGCCCAGGACCAUCAAGCGCACGCGGCGGCGUCUGUCCCGCAACCGCGACCCGGGGCGCCUCAUCCUCAGCACCAUCCGCCUGCGGCCGCGCCAGGUGCUCUGUGAGAAGUGCAAGAGCACGCUGAGCCCCCCGGAGGCCAGCCCCGGACCCCCAGCCGCGCCCAGGGCCCGCAGGAGGCUGGGCAGCGGCCCGGACAGGGAGCUCCGCAAGCCGGAGGAGCCGGAGAACGGCGAGCCCACGGCUGCGGCCACCGCCAGGAGGAGCAAGAGGGAGAGGCGCGAGGAGGACAGGGCCCCGGCAGAGCAGGUCCCGCGGAGCCCGGUCAUCAAGAUCUCCUACAGCACGCCCCAGGGCAAGGGAGAGGUGGUCAAGAUCCCCUCCCGCGUGCACGGCUCUCUGGAGCCCUUCCGUCCCCAGCAGGCCCCGCAGGACGACGGCAGCCAGGACCCCGAGGUGCUGGACAGAGAGUCCCGGGACCGGCCGUCCUGCGCGCCCUCGGCCUCCAUCCCCAAGUUGAAACUGACACGGCCUGUGCCGGCCGGCGCGGACCUGCCGCCCCCUAAGAUCCGCCUGAAGCCCCACCGUCUGGGGGACAGCGAGCACGAGCCCGUGUACCGGGCCGAGCUGGUGGGGGAGCUGAACGGGUACCUGCGGGACAGCUCGCCGGCGCCCUGUGCGGACGGCCCUGCCGGUGGGCUGGCGGACUUGUCUUCUGGAAGUUCGGGUGAGGACGAUGACUUCAAGAGCUGUCCCCAGGGUCCACAGGGACGCGAGGGCUUGGCUUUUCUCGUCAGCUGCCCUGAGGGGAGAGCGGACUGUGCCAGUGAGUCGGCGUGCAGCAGCGACAGCCUGGACGAGGCCAGAUCGUCCGGCUCGGAAGGGACGCCGGCAGACACGGGUGACCUCUCGCCUGGCCACGGCGCGUCAGCGCCCUCGGUGUCCAGAGAGGCUCGCCAAACGGUGCCGCCCCUGACGGUCAGGCUGCACACACAGAGCGUGUCGGAGUGCAUCACGGAGGACGGCAGGACUGUGGCCGUGGGGGACAUCGUCUGGGGUAAGAUCCAUGGUUUUCCUUGGUGGCCGGCGCGUGUUCUUGACAUCAGUCUCGGCCAGAAGGAGGACGGAGAGCCGUCUUGGCGAGAAGCGAAGGUCUCGUGGUUUGGUUCUCCGACUACGUCGUUCUUGUCUAUUUCAAAACUCUCCCCUUUCUCUGAAUUUUUCAAACUGAGAUUUAAUCGUAAGAAGAAGGGGAUGUAUCGGAAAGCUAUAACCGAGGCUGCAAAUGCCGCAAGACACGUGGCCCCGGAAAUCAGGGAGCUCUUAACCCAGUUUGAAACGUAACUGGUUCCCUGACCA